GACAUCAACCCGGCACCUGCCAACAUGGAAGGUGGCGGCGGCAGCGUCGCUGUAGCUGGCCUCGGAGCUCGAGGCUCUGGAGCGGCUGCAGCUACAGUCCGGGAACUUCUGCAGGACGGGUGUUAUAGUGACUUUUUAAACGAAGACUUUGAUGUAAAGACUUAUACUUCUCAAUCUAUUCAUCAAGCUGUAAUUGCUGAACAACUAGCAAAACUUGCCCAAGGAAUCAGUCAGUUGGACAGAGAACUACACUUACAGGUUGUUGCAAGACAUGAAGAUUUACUGGCACAAGCAACUGGGAUUGAGUCGUUGGAAGGUGUUCUUCAGAUGAUGCAGACGAGAAUUGGGGCUUUACAGGGAGCUGUUGAUAGGAUAAAAGCAAAAAUUGUUGAACCAUACAAUAAGAUAGUUGCCCGGACUGCACAACUAGCAAGACUUCAGGUUGCCUGUGAUUUGCUUCGGAGGAUUAUUCGUAUCUUGAAUCUCAGUAAGAGACUCCAAGGACAACUGCAAGGGGGAAGUAGAGAGAUAACAAAAGCUGCUCAGAGUCUCAAUGAACUUGAUUAUCUUUCUCAAGGAAUAGAUCUUUCUGGAAUAGAAGUGAUAGAAAAUGAUCUACUUUUUAUUGCAAGAGCCCGACUUGAAGUGGAAAAUCAAGCUAAGCGCCUACUAGAGCAGGGUUUGGAGACUCAGAAUCCAACUCAAGUCGGAACAGCUCUUCAGGUUUUCUAUAAUCUUGGAACUUUGAAGGAUACUAUUACCAGUGUUGUGGAUGGAUAUUGUGCUACUUUAGAAGAAAAUAUCAACAGUGCAUUAGACAUAAAAGUUUUGACUCAGCCUUCCCAGUCAGCUGUGAGAGGGGGACCUGGACGAUCUACCAUGCCAACCCCAGGAAAUACUGCAGCUUUGCGUGCCUCAUUCUGGACCAAUAUGGAGAAACUUAUGGAUCAUAUUUAUGCUGUUUGUGGACAGGUACAACAUCUACAAAAAGUAUUGGCCAAGAAGAGAGAUCCUGUUUCUCACAUUUGUUUCAUUGAAGAAAUAGUUAAGGAUGGACAACCGGAAAUUUUCUACACAUUUUGGAAUUCAGUUACUCAGGCACUUUCUUCUCAAUUUCAUAUGGCAACAAACUCUUCGAUGUUUUUGAAGCAGGCAUUUGAAGGAGAAUACCCUAAAUUAUUACGUCUUUAUAAUGACUUAUGGAAGCGUCUUCAACAAUACAGUCAGCAUAUCCAAGGGAAUUUUAAUGCAAGUGGAACUACAGACCUCUAUGUUGACCUACAACACAUGGAAGAUGAUGCACAAGAUAUAUUCAUACCAAAAAAGCCAGAUUAUGAUCCAGAAAAGGCUUUGAAAGACUCACUACAACCCUAUGAGGCUGCUUAUCUAUCAAAAUCCUUAUCUCGACUCUUCGAUCCUAUCAACUUGGUUUUUCCCCCGGGUGGUCGUAAUCCUCCUUCCUCUGAUGAACUUGAUGGUAUUAUUAAAACUAUAGCAAGUGAACUAAAUGUUGCUGCUGUUGAUACAAACCUCACAUUAGCUGUGUCAAAAAAUGUGGCAAAGACCAUCCAGUUAUACAGUGUAAAAUCAGAGCAGCUUCUCUCCACACAAGGAGAUGCAAGUCAGGUGAUUGGGCCUCUUACUGAAGGACAGAGAAGAAAUGUGGCAGUAGUGAAUUCAUUGUAUAAGUUGCACCAAUCAGUAACAAAGGUUGUUUCCAGUCAGAGCUCAUUCCCACUGGCAGCUGAGCAAACUAUAAUUUCAGCUCUAAAGGCUAUUCAUGCUCUUAUGGAAAAUGCUGUGCAACCCUUACUCACUUCUGUGGGAGAUGCUAUAGAGGCCAUAAUCAUCACCAUGCAUCAAGAAGACUUUUCUGGGUCAUUAUCCAGCUCAGGAAAACCUGAUGUUCCUUGUUCUCUGUACAUGAAGGAGCUACAAGGUUUCAUUGCCAGAGUUAUGAGUGACUAUUUUAAACACUUUGAAUGCUUGGAUUUUGUCUUUGACAACACUGAGGCUAUUGCCCAAAGAGCUGUUGAACUUUUUAUCCGCCAUGCCAGUCUCAUAAGACCUCUUGGUGAAGGUGGGAAAAUGCGACUUGCUGCUGAUUUUGCACAGAUGGAGUUGGCUGUGGGUCCAUUCUGUAGACGAGUAUCUGAUUUAGGAAAGUCCUAUCGGAUGCUGAGAUCAUUCAGACCUCUGCUCUUCCAGGCAAGUGAACAUGUAGCCAGUAGUCCUGCAUUGGGGGAUGUGAUUCCGUUCAGCAUCAUUAUUCAGUUUUUGUUCACGAGAGCACCCGCUGAACUGAAAUCUCCUUUCCAGAGGGCAGAGUGGUCCCACACACGCUUCUCUCAGUGGCUGGAUGACCAUCCAUCUGAAAAGGACAGGCUCCUCCUCAUCAGGUAAAGCCAGGUGCUCUGGGGGCACCCAUCUGGUCUGGAAGCCCAAGGAGGGUGGGGAUGCAAGAGAGGAUGAAGGAGCAGUGCCUGGGGGCAUGGACAUGUGACUGCACCUUCCAGUGGCGGGCCACCUCACUGCCUAGGCACGGGUGCUGGAGCAACCAGCAGUUGGAAAUGUUGGCCACAACAUCUUUUGCUUUCUUUCAUUCCAAACCUUCAUAUCCCUGAUGUGCAAUCCUGUGUCCCAUGCAACCCUAAGGACCAUGCAUUUGUACCUUUGAAAAUCAUCAUUUGCUAUGAAAAGUUUUGCCCUAGCUCCGCAUCUUUUACUUCAUUUUUAUGUGCUGCAGUUACUGAAUUGGUGGAACACAGAUGUGAGUGAAUUUUUAAAAAUACCCAAGUGCGAAACAGUUCUGAGGAGGAAACAAGAACAACCCAGCAGCCACUUGGAUACCAUGGCCCUCCAGUAGUGCCCCAUGAAUGCAUUCACAUACAUACGCAUGUGCUCUUGCCCACACGUGCACACACCCCCAUGUACCCCAACCAUGCCCAGGGUGGGGUGCUUUAACUGUCAUACAUGGCUUAUUAAGCAACACUCUUCCCUGCAACUGCUCUCACCAUCACCAGAGACCUCUCAGCCACCAAACAUUCCCAUUUUUACCUUACCACUCUGUAGCUUUAGCUACAGUUGACCGCCAUUUCCUUCUGUAAACUCAUAAACUGGGACUCAGCACAUUUUUAUUGAUGCUGAGCUCACAUUUUAUCAGCAUGGUAGGCCCUGGGCCAGGAACCGAGGAUACGAAGUAAGCCGAGAUAUGGCCCUGUCCUCUCAGAGCUUGCAUUACACCACAGCCAUCUGUUUCUGUUCUAACUUCUCUGGCCAUUUUUUUUUGUGUGUCAUUUGCUGAAUUAUCUUCUUCUAGCCAUUCCUUAAAUGCUAUCAUUUCCCAUAUUUUCUUCUUCUCAUCCUGCCUCUGCCUUGGUUCCCAGGUGAGCUUGUCCAGACCCAUGCCUCUAGUGCCCCUUCUAUACUUAAGAGCCCUCAGGUCUGUGACUGCCUCUGGAUGGGGCCUUGGCCCAGUAAACUUGCUAUCAUAUGUCACCACCCACAGAAAUCUCAACCCCAGAAUGGUCAAAAUAAUUCUAAUCUUUUCUCUCAAACCUUCUCAUUCUCUUAUACUCCCUGUCUUGGUUGGGAGGUCACAAUCACCUAACUAGCCAAGCCGGAAAACCUUUACAUCAUCAUUCAACUCCUCUGUCAUCCUUAUUCCUCAAACCCACUCUGUUGCGUCUCUAAAAUAGCUCUUGAAGUCAUUCUCAACUCUCCCAGGGGAUCCCAAUUCUGUUGGUCUGGGCCCACUGCACCCAGUGAUCCUUUGUUAGCCUGUGUCAGGUGAUGAGUUGAGUUCCCUAAAGCCAGAGUGGGGCUGACAUGAUGAGGUGGUUCUAAACCACAUGUGCACACAAGAAUCAUUUACAUAGCUUGGAAAAUUCCUAGUGCCCAGGUCUCUCACCCUUGCCUACCUCAGAAUCUCCAGGGUAGGCCUGCUAUCAGGAUUUCUCUAUAGCUCCCCAAGAAGGUCCAGGGUGCAGCCAAGGGCGUGAACCCCUGCCAUAGUGGGUCAUAUUUCAGUUAGGAUGAAAGACUGCUGAGGAAGCUAUGACAGGUCAGUAAGAACCAUCAGCCUGUCAGCUUUGUUUCCAGAAGUGACCCUGAGCCCUCAAGCUUGGUACCCACAUCCCACAUGAGCCACUGGCCCUCUGGGCGUAUGUGUGGAUAAAGAUUAGCUCGGACCCUGCUCUUUUUCCUUGCUUAUCUGUUACUCAGCUAUGAACAUCUGACACAGAAAUGGGAGAGGUUACCAGCCCCGGUGAAUGUUCCUGGUAAAAUCUGCCCUCGGGAAAGGCUUUGGAUUUGGGUGAGGAGUUUGGGCCUGGGCUAACACAGGGAUUUGCAAUGUCUGUGUGGAUUAUUUUUCCCGAGUCCCAAAGAUUCACUCAGCUGCAACACACUCAGUCGUCUUAAAAAGAGGAUUCAGUUAAUUGAACACGUUCAUUUUUCUCAUCUUAACAAGUUGGUCAUUUUUGUCGUCUUAACAAGUUGGAAUGAGUUCAUCCAAAACAGUUGUCCUGCUGUGUGUACAUCACAAAUCUGUUUUCUUUUGCUUCUCUUUAAAAAUGUCUCCUGAGUGAUUUCAUCAGCAGUGCUGUUGCUAAGCCUAUAUUUAGCAACUGAAAAUCAUGCUCAGAAAUACUGUCAUGCUUUUUUAAAAAGGCAUAUCCAUCCCUCCACACAUGGCUGAUUCCAGAACCUUCAUGCCCUUAGCAAAAAAUUGAGCUGUCCUUCAGGGUUUCAAAAAAAGUACUGUACUCCUGCUGCACCCCAGGCUCUUGGCAAGGAGGGGACUUUUGUCCUAGAGAAUGUUCUUUCUUAUGUAUUAUUGCAAAACAAUUUUGUUCUUGCAUACUGAAGCAUCACUGGAUGAAUUUCUUUCCCCUGUAGACAAACCGAGGGUGAGUAUUGCUCUUUAAAUGUCAGUAAAUUUGUUUUAGCUUCUGGGGCAAACCUUGUUGUAUACUCAUUCUGUUCCUCCCAGCAUAAUAUGUUAGGUUGUCAUAAAAUAGGGCAAAUUGAGGAUAGUGUAACUACUGCUGCUGAAUAAAUGGGAAAUAGUGAACCAUCCUGCCUUCCUGUUUUCUUCUGACACCAGAUGCUUUCUGGAGCUUAAAUGAAUACUAGUCAAGUUCAUUUGAAAAUCAGAGUAAUAACUUACUCAUGGGACCAAGUGGUGUAAAUGGGGGCAGUUGUAUGUGUUCAGCCUGCAUCAGGCAGGUGCUCCAGACACGUGUGCUCCCUCAGAUGCAGAGGCAGCCGCCUGGCUCGUGCCUGUGGGUAAGUGUUGAAUGUGUUUUCAAUAAAGAUAGAGUCUUUGAUGGAAAGAUUUCUCAAGCUCUGUAACAGCGGUGGGGUUGGCCUCAAAUCCAUUUACUCUGGAUAUUUGCCGUGGAGAGCAACUCUUCUUCUUAUGGCCCUCUUUGAGUAGGAGUACACAAAUGUUCACAGACCUUAUUAGCCUAGUGGUACUUUUAUCUACACCAUCAGAGAAUGCUUGGUGCCAUGUGCAUCCUUGGAUCCCUUGCCCUCUUGCCAUGGUCCAGGGUCCACAAUCUGGAAGCCAUUCCCUCAGCUCCUCUGUACUUCUGCAGAACUCCCAAGAUCUCCAUCGAUGGAGGGAAAUGUUUCUCCUCCUGGUACCAUGUCACUAGCUACCUAUCAGUUCUGUGAAUGGAGUGUCUGAAAUAGGACGAAGAGGGAGGAUGGAACCAGGGAAAAGCCUGGGCUUAACUGCUUAUUGAGGCAUGUAGUGUAUCUUUAAGUCAUUUAUGCAUUUCAGUACUUACUAAUCACAUUGAAUAUUUAAAUGCCUGACAAAAAUCAAUGUUGUUUUCCAUGAAAACUUCCACUUGGCUAGUUUUUGUCAUGUUGAGCAGUGUUGCCAUGUUACCACAAACCAUUCCUCUACUAAUCGUGUUUUUUUUCUCAAUAAGGAUAACCUCAAUAAUCUACUUAUUUUGGUUACAAACCAGAGUUAAGACUAACUGUUACAUAACACUUGGCCUGACUUCCAAGAAAGCUAAUGUUUUGCUUAAGCAAAUGAAGUAAUUUAAUAAGUACUCGAAAAUCUUGCUCUAAUUUCAUGUGGGAGGGCAGCUUAAUCUUUUUUGCCCCAUACUUCUGAUGGUGUUUUUGAUGACUACCCAAAAAUCUAACCAAACUCAUUUCUGAUCUCUUCUACAUGUUGUGUAACUUACGUGAUGUCUUAUCCUUUUAAAUGCCAACGAAACUAAGUUGAUUUUUGUCCAUCAAAUAUAUCUAAUCCAUUCACUAUGAAA